AGACACACACACCAGCAGCUACACCUACACGCUGACCAUCACAGGCACACAGAGGCACAUCCACCUCACAUCCACCUCAUACUUGUGUACUCUCAGGGUUCAGUCUUUCAUCCUAUCCCUCUCUGAUCUGUGCCUCCCAAUACCUUCCAAGAUGUUUACAGAGACCCUUCUCCCUGUGCAGUUAGGAGUGUAAGGCAAGAGAGCCCCUACUUCAUGGGGCAGAUCAAGAGCUGAGACCAAAGAUGGUCUAUGUUGCUGACCUUGUCCUGUCCUCCUGCUGUCUUAAACUAUGAUCCCUGCUGCGGUCACUGAAGCCUUUCCCUAGCAGGAAGAAAAUCUCAUUUGAAAAGCCCAGAACUAUUCUGUUACACAGAAGACCAGGAAAGAGAAGUUUAAAACCAAGUCUAAGAAAAGUCCCCAGGGUCACACAGUUCAUAAGCGACAGAGCCAGGAUUCCAGCACCUGGUCUGAAUGACCCAGAAGCCAGGACUUUUCCCCCGCACCUCUACAUCAGGCGUGCUGGAGCAGGAAGCGGUCAGGCAGCCCCACUAGGAGUAACAAAGAUGGGAUCACAGAGCCUUGGAACUGGGGGUGGCUCCUUCAUGAGACCAUGGUGCCACCUACUGGCAGAAAGAGAAGGGGUGUACACAGAGCGCUAAGAGAAGACUGGGAAGGAGAAAAAGAAAAAGAUGGGGAAGGAGAGGAGAUGGAAAGAUGAAGGGAGGGGAAAAAUGGGGAAUGUGAGGUUUCAUGGAGGGAAGAGGAUUAGGAACUAUUUGCUACUCGCAGGAGAGAGCGGAAGCUGCCAAAUCUCAGUCAUUUCCUUGAAAGUGAGCAGUGGUGUGUGAGAGCCAGGCGUCCCUCUGCCUGCCCACUCAGUGGCAACACCCGGGAGCUGUUUUGUCCUUUGUGGAGCCUCAGCAGUUCCCUCUUUCAGAACUCACUGCCAAGAGCCCUGAACAGGAGCCACCAUGCAGUGCUUCAGCUUCAUUAAGACCAUGAUGAUCCUCUUCAAUUUGCUCAUCUUUCUGUGUGGUGCAGCCCUGUUGGCAGUGGGCAUCUGGGUGUCAAUCGAUGGGGCAUCCUUUCUGAAGAUCUUCGGGCCACUGUCGUCCAGUGCCAUGCAGUUUGUCAACGUGGGCUACUUCCUCAUCGCAGCCGGCGUUGUGGUCUUUGCUCUUGGUUUCCUGGGCUGCUAUGGUGCUAAGACUGAGAGCAAGUGUGCCCUCGUGACGUUCUUCUUCAUCCUCCUCCUCAUCUUCAUUGCUGAGGUUGCAGCUGCUGUGGUCGCCUUGGUGUACACCACAAUGGCUGAGCACUUCCUGACGUUGCUGGUAGUGCCUGCCAUCAAGAAAGAUUAUGGUUCCCAGGAAGACUUCACUCAAGUGUGGAACACCACCAUGAAAGGGCUCAAGUGCUGUGGCUUCACCAACUAUACGGAUUUUGAGGACUCACCCUACUUCAAAGAGAACAGUGCCUUUCCCCCAUUCUGUUGCAAUGACAACGUCACCAACACAGCCAAUGAAACCUGCACCAAGCAAAAGGCUCACGACCAAAAAGUAGAGGGUUGCUUCAAUCAGCUUUUGUAUGACAUCCGAACUAAUGCAGUCACCGUGGGUGGUGUGGCAGCUGGAAUUGGGGGCCUCGAGUUCUUUUCCAACUCAGCUCGAAGGCCACCUCUUCCAGAAAGCCUCUAUAGCACUCCCAUCAGAAGAGAUCACGUCUUUCUACAACCCUCCCCUCCAUGACUUUCAUGGCUCUUAGAGCCUCUGCUGUCUCUGCUUCAUCCUGGAAGUAUCACAAUCCUCCACCACACUGAACCCCUCAAGGUAGGGCCAGGUCUGAUUACUUUCAGGUCCCCAGUGCCCAGCACAAGGCUGAGGCCAAAGAAAGGACCAGGGGAUGGUUAUAAAAUAAAUCAAUGAAUUGACUGCCUA